GACGGCCCCGGAUGAGGAACUCGGAGGAGGAGCUGGGCCCGCGCGUCCAUGAUUCGAAGGCUCGUUUUCGCAGCUUUUCCACGUCUUUUUCCGGUCCCACUGCCCUCCAUGCUAACUCACUGGGCGUCUCUAGCCGUUAUACCAACAAUGACUGCGACCAGUGUUGGGAAAGCGCCCCCUGGGCCCCUCCCUGACGCCAGCCCAUCCUUGAGACUCCCUGCAAGGAGGCGGCCCGACCCAGUGGGUCCCCAGGACAAUAGAUGACACAGUACUUCUUCCUCUUCAUAACGGCCAUUUUAAUAUCCUAGGAGAGCUAAAGGUUUGGAGUUCUUCCUGAGUUGCCAUUUCCCCACCUAGAACCCUUCACAGGUUGUACCUAUUAGCAAUGUGAUGGGAAACCAUUUCAGCAGCAAAGGUGAGUGAGCUAUGGCAGUGAGGCACAUCGCGUCCAAGUUUUAGCUGACUCAGGCAAUUGGCUCCAGUGAGAGGACCACAAAAGGUACCCACUUAAAGAGGCCACUUCCCACCAGUACUCAUCAAAACAUAACAAAGUGUUAAGAAACAGCAGCUGCUAUUUUGCUUUUGAGCAAAAUUUUCUUUUAACAGUUUGCCAGAUGACAGAGGUGGAAACAACUCAAAAAAUUGUUACCUUUUUUCGUUUUUGUCUUUUUGUUGUUGUUGAGACAGAGUCUUGCUCUGUCGCCCAGGCUGGAGUGCAGUGGCGCGAUCUCAGCUCACUGCAACCUCCAGCUCCCAGGUUCAAGCAUUUUCCCUGCCUCAGCCUCCAGAGUAGAUGGGAUUACAGGUGGGCACCACCACACCUAGCUAAUUUUUGUAUUUUUAGUAGAGAUGGGGUUUCACCAUGUUGGCCAGGCUGGUCUCAAACUCCUGACCUCGGGUGAUCCGCCCGUCUUGGCCUCCCAAAGUGCUGGGAUUACAGGCGUGAGCCACUGCACCGAGCCUGUUUUGUUUUUUUUAGUGCAAAUUAACAAACUGAUUCUAAAGUUUAUAUAGAAAUGCUAAGGAUUUAGGAUUGCCAAAACAAUUUUGAAAAAGAAUAAAAUUGGAAUACUUGUAUUUUUUUAAGAUUUUUUUCCUAAAGGUACAGUAAUCAGGAUGGUAUGGUAUCAGCAUAGAGACAAAUAGAUCAACAGAGCAGAACAGAAAGUCCAGAAAUAUGAGGUUGAAUUUCUUAAAGAAAAAAAAGUCCAGAAAUAGAUCUAGAUACAUACAAUAGCUGAUUUUUUAUAAAUUACUAAGGUAAUUCUGCAUCUAGCUAAGCUGAAAAUUAGGCCGAGGAUCUGUUUGUAACAGUGACAGUAAUGUAAAGGAGACCAAUUGUGCAGACUCGGCAGGUCCCCUGAGUCAAAGUCGUGGCUCAUACAGGGAGAGGGUGGGAUCCUGAGACCUGUUCUCUGUCACAGUGUAGUCCGCAGGAACUUUACCCAACCAUCAUGAUGGUCCAUAUAUUGAUGACAAAUGCUAGUAGUACCCAGUGAGCAGCAAGUGACAAGGGUCAUAAAUAUCCUAGUAAGACUUCUUACUAAGGCAGUACAGAAACCUGAAGAUAUGGGCACUUAUCAAAUGGAUGAAGUUUUGGUGGGGCCCAGUGGUUUGGGGACAUCACCCAAAGGUAAAAGAAAGUUGUUCCACCUUGCACCCUCUAAUCCCAAAAAAAUUGGUACAGGUCCUGGUGGGCCCCUUUGGAUUUGGGAGGUAGCAUAUUCUGCACCUGAGAAAACUGUUCCAACACAUGUAUUAGGUGACCUAAAAAGCUUCCACUUUUUAUUUAUUACUAUUUUUUUUUCUUGACACGGAGUCUUGCUCUGUAGCCCAGGCUGGAGUACAGUGCCGUGAUCUCGGCUCACUGCAACCUCUGCUUUCUGGAUUCAAGCAAUUCUCCUGCCUCAGCCUCCCUAGUAGCUGGGAUUACAGGCGCCCGCCACCAUGCCCAGCAUUUUUGUAUUUUAGUAGUGGAGGGGUUUCACCAUGUUAGCCAGGCUGAUCUUGAACUCCUGACCUCAAGCAAUCCACCCACCUCCGCCUCCCAAAGUGCUGGGAUUACAGACGUGAGCCACCAUGCCUGGCCAGCUUCCACUUUUUAUUGGGGCAAGAGAGCACUCUAUAGUAAAUCCAAGCAACAGUGCAAGCUUACUUGCAAAUUCAGUGGUUCCAGAAAUAUCCUUGAUGGAUACAGGUGCUGUAUGGAGUUGCUGGCAAACCCCAAUAAGAGUGUGCAUUCGUGUGCUAGGGCUCCUAUAACAAAGUACCACAAACUGGGUGGCUUAAACAACAGAAAUCUGUUGGUUCACAGUCUGGAGGCUAGAAGUCAGAAAUUAAGGUGUGGUUCCUAUUGAGGCUGUGAGAAGGAAUCUGUCCAUGCCUCUCUCCUAGUUUCUGGGGAUUUGCUGGAUAUAUUUUGCAUUCCUUGGCAUCGUAAGAAGCAUUUUCCCAGUCUUUACCCUCAUCUUCAUUUGGCAUUCUCCCUGUGUACUAUCUCUAAACUUCCCUUUUUUAUAAGGAUACCAGUCAUUAGAUGAGGGACCCACCCUAAUCCACUAUGACCUCAUCUUGAAGUAAUUACAUCUGCAAUGCCUCUAUUGCCAAAUAAUUUCACAUUCUGAGGUAUUAGGGGCUAGAACUUCAACCUGUUAAUUGGGGAUGAGGUGGAGGUACAAUUCAACCCAUCAUAAAGAGUCACAGCACAAAUACCUAAGAUUCUGGAGCAAGGUCAUGCCUUCUAAGGCAAAAAAACAAAACCCACGUUUCCAAACUCCCAGGAUAGCAAAACCUGAUCUCAUAAAACCUAGGUCACAAAGGACAGCCCUGCAAAACAGACCCUAUUUGGAUCAAGUGAGCCAGUUCCUGGAACCUGAAUAAUGACUCCUGAAUCAAGGGAUACUACAGAUUUGUCUCCAGGGGGUACCCAGGAGAUGGAAGGCAUCGUGAUAGUGAAGGUGGAGGAGGAAGAUGAAGAAGACCAUUUUCAAAAGGAAAGAAACAAAGUAGAGUCAUCGCCACAAGUUCUCAGUCGCUCUACAACUAUGAAUGAGAGAGCCUUAUUGUCAUCGUAUUUAGUUGCAUAUAGAGUGGCAAAAGAGAAAAUGGCUCACACAGCGGCUGAAAAAAUUAUCCUUCCAGCAUGUAUGGACAUGGUACGGACAAUUUUUGAUGACAAAUCAGCUGAUAAACUAAGAACUAUACCUCUUAGUGAUAAUACAAUAUCUCGUCGAAUCUGUACGAUUGCAAAACAUUUGGAAGCAAUGCUUAUUACACGGCUGCAGUCCGGUAUAGACUUUGCAAUCCAACUCGAUGAGAGCACUGAUAUUGCAAGUUGUCCCACACUCUUGGUUUAUGUCAGAUAUGUGUGGCAAGAUGAUUUUGUAGAGGAUCUCUUAUGUUGUUUAAAUUUAAAUUCACAUAUAACUGGAUUAGAUUUAUUUACUGAAUUAGAAAACUGCCUUCUUGGUCAGUAUAAAUUAAACUGGAAACAUUGUAAAGGAAUUUCAAGUGAUGGAACAGCAAAUAUGACCGGAAAACACAGCAGACUUACUGAAAAAUUGUUAGAAGCAACCCACAACAAUGCUGUUUGGAAUCACUGUUUUAUUCAUCGAGAAGCUUUGGUAUCCAAAGAAAUUUCACCAAGUCUGAUGGAUGUAUUGAAAAAUGCAGUGAAAACUGUUAAUUUUAUUAAAGGAAGCUCACUGAAUAGCCGACUUCUCGAAAUAUUUUGUUCAGAGAUUGGAGUGAACCACACCCACUUAUUGUUUCAUACAGAAGUUCGUUGGCUUUCUCAAGGAAAAGUAUUGAGCAGAGUAUAUGAACUCAGGAACGAGAUUUACAUUUUUCUCGUUGAAAAGCAAUCUCAUUUGGCAAAUAUUUUUGAAGACGACAUUUGGGUAACAAAAUUGGCAUAUUUAAGUGAUAUUUUUGGCAUUCUUAAUGAAUUAAGCCUGAAAAUGCAGGGGAAAAACAAUGAUAUAUUUCAGUAUCUUGAACAUAUUCUAGGAUUCCAAAAGACGUUAUUAUUGUGGCAAGCAAGACUUAAAAGUAACCGCCCUAGCUACUAUAUGUUUCCAACAUUAUUGCAACACAUCGAAGAGAACAUUAUUAAUGAAGACUGCUUAAAAGAAAUAAAAUUAGAGAUAUUGUUGCAUCUCACUUCUUUGUCUCAAACUUUUAAUUAUUACUUUCCGGAAGAGAAAUUUGAAUCAUUAAAGGAAAAUAUUUGGAUGAAAGAUCCAUUUGCUUUUCAAAACCCAGAAUCAAUAAUUGAGUUAAACUUGGAGCCUGAAGAAGAGAAUGAAUUAUUGCAGCUCAGUUCAUCAUUCACACUAAAGAAUUAUUAUAAGAUAUUAAGUUUAUCAGCAUUUUGGAUUAAGAUUAAAGAUGACUUUCCACUGCUAAGUAGGAAGAGUAUAUUGCUGUUACUACCAUUCACAACUACAUAUUUGUGUGAACUAGGAUUUUCAAUCUUGACACGGUUAAAAACAAAGAAGAGAAAUAGGCUCAAUAGUGCACCAGAUAUGCGGGUAGCAUUAUCUUCAUGUGUUCCUGACUGGAAGGAACUUAUGAACAGACAAGCACACCCAUCACAUUAAAUACAAACUUUACAAAAUUCUGUGUAUAGCCAGGUGUGGUGGCUUACGCCUGUAAUCCCAGCAGUGGGAGACCGAGGUGGGCAGAUCACUUGAGUUCAAGACCAGCCUGGCCAACAUGGUGAAACCCCAUCUCUACUAAAAAUAGAAACCUUAGCCAGGCGUGGUGGCACAUGCCUGCAGUCCCAGUUACUUGGGUGCCUGAGGCAGGAGAAUCUCUUAAACCAGGAAGGCAGAGAUUGCAGUGAGCUGAGAUAAUCCCACUGCAUUCCAGCCUGGGCAACAGCGUGAGACUUCAUCUCAAAAAAAAAAAAUUGUAUUUGUACUUUUAAAGGGAUUUUGCAGUAUGUUGUAGUUAAACGUUAAUAAAAUUAUAUUUGUAAUUAGGA